AGACCACCAGCUAAUGGAUGCGGAGCGGAGGGCCCGCUGACCGCUCUCCGCGCCUGGGUAAGUAUCGGGCAGGGCACGCGGAGUGAGGACCGGAGGACGCAGCCCCCAGCCCCAGUGCCCCUCUCCUCCACCUGCCUGGCCCAGGCGCCUCUGCCCCGCCGCAUGGCGGAGGUGGGCCGGGGGCGAGGGCGCACUGUGGAUAGGGGUCCCGCCCCGUUACCCUGGGUGUGAGCUGAUGGAUGGGAAAAGGGGACAAGCCGGGCGCCAGGCUACUCAGGGUGUGGGAAGCGGGAUGGCACUGAAGAUGAGCAAGGAUAGCACAGGCAGGGUGGACAGGAGGGGGGCAGCCAAGACGCUGGACACCCCAGCUUCAGUUUGUCCACUCGCCUUGGCAGGCUGCAGGGAGCAGAGACUGAAACGAGAAGGUUCCCGCUUCGUGCAUCCACUUUGGUGUGGUUGGGGUGACGGGGGAGUGGGGGGGGGGCACACAACAUGGCGGGAAGAAAUUCAGAGGGGCGUAGCAGAUGGGAGAGGAAUAUAGAGAGAGACGCAGGUCUGCGGUCUAUGGGGGUGUAGCAAAGAGUGCAGUCGGGAAUUCCAGCCCAGGGCCACGACUUAAAGACGGGGUGCAGACCGACUCUAUUGCGCAAGGCGCCAUGGACCGUGUCUGCGCCACUGCGCCAAGAAGGGCGCAGGAACGUGUCGCGAUUUGGUUUAUUCUGCUUCCUCCACCAAAAAAAAAAAAAAAAAAAAAAAAAGAGAGAAAAAACAAACUGAAACCCCCUUCCCAAAUCUCCAGCUUUCCCCUGCGCCCCAGAGCCCCGCCUGGUUCCCCCGCCCCUGUUGCGCACUGCGCCACAGUCGCAGCGUUUCCCGGGUUACCAGAUGCCACGUGUUUGGGGAGUAAGUGCGGGUGCGCAUCUGGUGCGGAGUAGGAGGUAGGAUGUGGGCUGUGAGUGCCAUGAAUUGUGUGGGGCCAAGCAGGGGAAAGGUGUGUAGGAACUUGGUGUGUGUGUGCAGUAGCUGAGCCACGGCCACCGGGUUGAGCAGCUUGGCUUGGCUGGAGCUAAGAGCCAGACACACCACUGUGUGGAGGUGGGUGAUGUCUUCCUGUGCUAAAAGGUGAAUAAAUAAGCUCCUCACCUCUCGCGGAACACUCGGGAACACAUCAACAGGGGUCCAAGCCGCCCUGCUGGGAGGCUUCUCUUCAAGAGUUCUGGGUCCCAGAGUGGAAGGCAUUUUCCCAUCAACUGGAGAGAGACGAAACAUCAGAGACCAGGAGGCUGUGGAGAAAGCAGCUGUCCCAGGUGCCUCAACUAUCAGAGAAGGGUCAGCGUCACGUGGCUGCCAGCAUCUUUGAGAAAAUCACUGGCAAUCGGACUUCAGAGCUGCGGGCACAGGUGUGGUUAGAACUGAGAUACGACCUGCCCACCUGGGUCAGGCCUAAAGACAAGAAGUCCUGAGUUCUUGCCACUGAGUAGGCCAGGGUCAUUUGUCCAGAAAACUUUGUGACUGUCUUUGAGUGACCUAGUCUGGGACCCAUUCAUUGGUGGGUUCUAAGGUUAGAAGCUCAUCCAGGAUAUUUUCAAUAUUAAGUCAGUGCAUAGCUGCACCACUAACAAAUUGGUGCCUGUAGAGUCAGAGUGGGUCAAUUCUUAGGACAAUGGCGCUGGCACUGUUAGAGGACUGGUGCAGGAUAAUGAGUGUGGAUGAGCAGAAGUCACUGAUGGUUACGGGGAUACCGGCGGACUUUGAGGAGGCUGAGAUUCAGGAGGUCCUUCAGGAGACUUUAAAGUCUCUGGGCAGGUAUAGACUGCUUGGCAAGAUAUUCCGGAAGCAGGAGAAUGCCAAUGCUGUCUUACUAGAGCUUCUGGAAGAUACUGAUGUCUCGGCCAUUCCCAGUGAGGUCCAGGGAAAGGGGGGUGUCUGGAAGGUGAUCUUUAAGACCCCUAAUCAGGACACUGAGUUUCUUGAAAGAUUGAACCUGUUUCUAGAAAAAGAGGGGCAGACGGUCUCGGGUAUGUUUCGAGCCCUGGGGCAGGAGGGCGUGUCUCCAGCCACAGUGCCCUGCAUCUCACCAGAAUUACUGGCCCAUUUGUUGGGACAGGCAAUGGCACAUGCGCCUCAGCCCCUGCUACCCAUGAGAUACCGGAAACUGCGAGUAUUCUCAGGGAGUGCUGUCCCAGCCCCAGAGGAAGAGUCCUUUGAGGUCUGGUUGGAACAGGCCACGGAGAUAGUCAAAGAGUGGCCAGUAACAGAGGCAGAAAAGAAAAGGUGGCUGGCGGAAAGCCUGCGGGGCCCUGCCCUGGACCUCAUGCACAUAGUGCAGGCAGACAACCCGUCCAUCAGUGUAGAAGAGUGUUUGGAGGCCUUUAAGCAAGUGUUUGGGAGCCUAGAGAGCCGCAGGACAGCCCAGGUGAGGUAUCUGAAGACCUAUCAGGAGGAAGGAGAGAAGGUCUCAGCCUAUGUGUUACGGCUAGAAACCCUGCUCCGGAGAGCGGUGGAGAAACGCGCCAUCCCUCGGCGUAUUGCGGACCAGGUCCGCCUGGAGCAGGUCAUGGCUGGGGCCACUCUUAACCAGAUGCUGUGGUGCCGGCUUAGGGAGCUGAAGGAUCAGGGCCCGCCCCCCAGCUUCCUUGAGCUAAUGAAGGUAAUACGGGAAGAAGAGGAGGAAGAGGCCUCCUUUGAGAAUGAGAGUAUCGAAGAGCCAGAGGAACGAGAUGGCUAUGGCCGCUGGAAUCAUGAGGGAGACGACUGAAAACCACCUGGGGGCAGGACCCACAGCCAGUGGGCUAAGACCUUUAAAAAAUUUUUUUCUUUAAUGUAUGGGACUGAAAUCAAACCAUGAAAGCCAAUUAUUGACCUUCCUUCCUUCCUUCCUUCCCUCCCUUCCUCCUUCUCUCCUUCUCUCCUCCUCUCUCCUCUCCUCUCCUCUCUUUCCUUCCUUCCUUCCUUUUUUCUUUUUCUCUUUCUUCUUUAUUUCUUGGGUCUCACUCUCAUCACCCAGGCUAGAGUGCAGUGGCACAAAAAUCUCGGCUCACUGCAGCCUUGACUUCCCAGGCUCAGGCUCAGGUGAUCCUCACACCUUAGCCUCCCAAGUACCUGGGACUACAGGCACGCACCACCAUGCCUAGCUAUUCUUUUGUAUUUUUGGUAGAGACAGGGUUUUGCUGUGUUGCUCAGGCUGGUCUGGAACCCCUAGGCUCAAAUGAUGUGCCCAACUCGGCCUCCCAAAGUGCUGGGAUUACAGGCAUGAACCGCCAUGCCUGGCCCUUGAUUUUUCUUUUUAAGAAAAAAAUAUCUAGGAGUUUCUUAGACCCUAUGUAGAUUAUUAAUGAACAAAAGAUUAAACUCCAAAUAUUAAAUAGUAAGCCUGAAGGAAUCUGAAACACUUGUACUUCCAAUUUUCUUUAAAUAAUCCCAAAUAGACCAGAAUUGGCCCAUACCAUAGAAGAAAGAAUUGGCAGUCAAAAAAAAAAAUACCUUUUGUAAUGUUUGAAAAAUAAAGCUGUUUGACUUGUCAGGUGUUUUCCUUUCUCAAAUCAGCAAAUUCUCUCUGAGUGCCUGGCUUUGUGAGACACUGUACAAGGAGUUACAAGACUACAGCUAUAACCUGCAGUUGAGCAGUUAUAAACCUACAAAAUGGGCCCUGCCCUCAGAGAGGUUCCAGUCUAGAUGAGGAGCUGAUCUAGACAGGUAAAAGGCUAACUAACCCUUUGUGUAAAUAAGUUCAUCACCCCAGUAAAAGUGUCAUCACCCAGUGAAUAGGACCACCUCUGCCUGCAGAUUUUUGUUGUUGUUGUUGUCAUUGUUGUUGUUGUUUUAACCUGGGAAGUGUUCUUCCUGCCUUUCUGCUAGGUGUCAGAUAGAUGGUCCCAGAGCUAGGUGCUGUGUCAGGCCCUGAAGACACAGAUGACUCAACCUAAGCUUUACUUUCCAGAGGUCCACAGCCUGAGAGGUGUCCCCAAAGAAAGGGGGACAUGAGGGGACUGCAUGCUUGAGAGCAGGGUUGUUUAGGGCAGGUUUGGAUUUAGUGAGCAGGCUGGUUUGCUUAGAGAAGGCUUUUAGUGGCAACAAAGGAUGAAGAGGAGAGAAAAGGAACUCACAUUUAUUGAGGGCCUACUGUGUGCAAAGUGUUUCAUGUAUAUCUCAUUGAAUGUAUACAGCCACCCUGUUGUGGUAUAAUUUUGCUCUUUAUAAAGAGAAAGACCGAAGCUCAGAUGAGUUAAGUGGUCUCCUCAACACCAAAAUGCCAAGAAGUGAUGGAGCCUAGACAGAAGCCCAGAACUUUCUGACUCACACUAGUCCAUCCUCUACCAUCACGAUGACUUUCAAAUUGUGCUCUGCAGUUCUGCAGAUUUUCUAGCAGUGCCAUCUCCAAAAUGUGUUUUAAACUCUUUAUUUUUUUAAUUAUUAUUAGUAUUAUUUUGAGACUGAGUCUUGCUCUAUCACCCAGGCUGGAGUGCAGUGGUGCAAUCUCAGCUCACUGCAACCUCCGCCUCCCAGGUUCAAGCGAUUUCGUGCCUCAGCCUCCCGAGUAGCUGGGAUUACAGGCACCCACCACCACGCCCAGCUAAUUUUUGUAUUUUUAGUAGAAAUGGGGUUUCACCAUGUUGGCCAGGCUGGUCUCGAACUCCUGACCUCAAGUGAUCCACUCACCUCGGCCUCCCAAAGUGCUGGGAUUACAGGUGUGAGCCACCAUGCCUGGGCUAAACUCUUUAAGUCUCUAGUAAAUGCAGCUAGAUUCAAAUGGGCUGAUAACCAAAUUUUAACACAUCAGCAUUCACCACCAGGUUUACUUUUAUUUUCAGAUUGGCUCAUUUUGUGCAGACCUUAGAGCAAAGUUUCCUUUAUGGUAUCUGUGUACGUAUCCAAACUUCUUUUAAUUGUUCACAGAUUUUAAAAGCGGUAGCACCACAUGGUUGUGUAGAUCAGACCUGUGUAUUUAGAUCAGACCUGUGUAUCACGUAAGUGUGUGAGUGCAGUGCAGAUGAGCACCAUUUAGUUAUAUGUGCUAGGCAAAUCUCCAACACAGUUGAUGUGUAGUCUUGUGGUAGAUUUGUGCAUACUGUAAGCAAAUUGCUUAGCUUCUCUAGACAUCAGUUUCCACAUCUGAAAAAUAAGAAGAUGAGAGUACACGGUUGUUAUGAACAAAUGACUUAAUGCUUUUUAAGCACGUUGCAUGACAUCUGGAACACAGAAAGCCCUCAAUACAUUGAAGCUCUUAGGAUUUUCACGAUGUUCCUGUCUGCUCAAUGCAUGCUUUCUUUAUUGUUCUGACAGUUGUGUGGUAACAAGCUAAUAUGCUUCCAGUUGACUUCCAGUCUACCCUGGUGUUAGAAACCGUUUCAUCUCUUAUUGUAAAUUUGAGUGCUUGUUGUUUUUUAUAUUUGUGAUGACUCUUCCAGCAGUUGUUGACAAUUGUUAGAGGUUUGACUUUUAAAUAAUUACUUAUUUUUUCUGAUUGUGGUUCAGUUUAACUGAAGAAUAUCCUGAGAUUGUAAGAAAAGCAUUUUUUAAAAGGUAUCACUUGUGAUCAUUUAUCUUUCUAAAUUCUAUUUUUAAUACUGUUCCACCAAAGUGAUGCAGUGGUUACCAUGACACCCUAAUUUCAUGUGUUUUUGUAUUUAUGAAAAUAGUUUCAUUGUCAUUUAUUGGCGGUAUACAAAGUAAAAUGUUAUAAAUGUGAAGUUAUAAAAUAAAUAUAUGCUAAUAAAA